AUAACCAUGCACACUACUAUAACCACCCUAACCCUGACUUCCCUAAUUCCCCCCAUCCUUACCACCCUCGUUAACCCUAACAAAAAAAACUCAUACCCCCAUUAUGUAAAAUCCAUUGUCGCAUCCACCUUUAUUAUCAGUCUCUUCCCCACAACAAUAUUCAUGUGCCUAGACCAAGAAGUUAUUAUCUCGAACUGACACUGAGCCACAACCCAAACAACCCAGCUCUCCCUAAGCUUCAAACUAGACUACUUCUCCAUAAUAUUCAUCCCUGUAGCAUUGUUCGUUACAUGGUCCAUCAUAGAAUUCUCACUGUGAUAUAUAAACUCAGACCCAAACAUUAAUCAGUUCUUCAAAUAUCUACUCAUCUUCCUAAUUACCAUACUAAUCUUAGUUACCGCUAACAACCUAUUCCAACUGUUCAUCGGCUGAGAGGGCGUAGGAAUUAUAUCCUUCUUGCUCAUCAGUUGAUGAUACGCCCGAGCAGAUGCCAACACAGCAGCCAUUCAAGCAAUCCUAUACAACCGUAUCGGCGAUAUCGGUUUCAUCCUCGCCUUAGCAUGAUUUAUCCUACACUCCAACUCAUGAGACCCACAACAAAUAGCCCUUCUAAACGCUAAUCCAAGCCUCACCCCACUACUAGGCCUCCUCCUAGCAGCAGCAGGCAAAUCAGCCCAAUUAGGUCUCCACCCCUGACUCCCCUCAGCCAUAGAAGGCCCCACCCCAGUCUCAGCCCUACUCCACUCAAGCACUAUAGUUGUAGCAGGAAUCUUCUUACUCAUCCGCUUCCACCCCCUAGCAGAAAAUAGCCCACUAAUCCAAACUCUAACACUAUGCUUAGGCGCUAUCACCACUCUGUUCGCAGCAGUCUGCGCCCUUACACAAAAUGACAUCAAAAAAAUCGUAGCCUUCUCCACUUCAAGUCAACUAGGACUCAUAAUAGUUACAAUCGGCAUCAACCAACCACACCUAGCAUUCCUGCACAUCUGUACCCACGCCUUCUUCAAAGCCAUACUAUUUAUGUGCUCCGGGUCCAUCAUCCACAACCUUAACAAUGAACAAGAUAUUCGAAAAAUAGGAGGACUACUCAAAACCAUACCUCUCACUUCAACCUCCCUCACCAUUGGCAGCCUAGCAUUAGCAGGAAUACCUUUCCUCACAGGUUUCUACUCCAAAGACCACAUCAUCGAAACCGCAAACAUAUCAUACACAAACGCCUGAGCCCUAUCUAUUACUCUCAUCGCUACCUCCCUGACAAGCGCCUAUAGCACUCGAAUAAUUCUUCUCACCCUAACAGGUCAACCUCGCUUCCCCACCCUUACUAACAUUAACGAAAAUAACCCCACCCUACUAAACCCCAUUAAACGCCUGGCAGCCGGAAGCCUAUUCGCAGGAUUUCUCAUUACUAACAACAUUUCCCCCGCAUCCCCCUUCCAAACAACAAUCCCCCUCUACCUAAAACUCACAGCCCUCGCUGUCACUUUCCUAGGACUUCUAACAGCCCUAGACCUCAACUACCUAACCAACAAACUUAAAAUAAAAUCCCCACUAUGCACAUUUUAUUUCUCCAACAUACUCGGAUUCUACCCUAGCAUCACACACCGCACAAUCCCCUAUCUAGGCCUUCUUACGAGCCAAAACCUGCCCCUACUCCUCCUAGACCUAACCUGACUAGAAAAGCUAUUACCUAAAACAAUUUCACAGCACCAAAUCUCCACCUCCAUCAUCACCUCAACCCAAAAAGGCAUAAUUAAACUUUACUUCCUCUCUUUCUUCUUCCCACUCAUCCUAACCCUACUCCUAAUCACAUAA